CCUGACCUCACGAUGACCAGGUGUGCUCUGCUGUUGCUGAUGGUCCUGAUGUUGGGCAGAGUCCUGGUUGUCCCAGUGACCCCUAUCCCAACCUUCCAGCUCCGCCCUCAGAAUUCUCCCCAGACCACUCCCCGACCUGCGGCCUCAGAGAGCCCCUCAGCUGCUCCCACAUGGCCGUGGGCUGCCCAGAGCCACUGCAGCCCCACCCGCCACCCUGGCUCGCGCAUUGUCCUAUCGCUGGAUGUCCCCAUCGGCCUCUUGCAGAUCUUACUGGAGCAAGCCCGGGCCAGGGCUGCCAGGGAGCAGGCCACCACCAACGCCCGCAUCCUGGCCCGUGUCGGCCACUGCUGAGCCUGAGAGAGGGGGUCACAGUGAUAGGGCCACCCUGGAUGGGAAGACCUGGAGGGCAGCCACACAGCUGGACGGAUGCUGCCACAUCUGGGCAUACAGUGUCUGGACGCUGCCACAUCUGGGCAUACAGUGUCUGGACACUGCCACAUGGAGCCACUGUCAUGCAGGUCAUAUCAGAUCUGAGUGCCCCACAGAGUCACAGUGUGUCUGGACAGCCUGGACAUUGGACAUUGCUAAGUUGGGUCACUGCCACAUGGAGUCUUGCCAUGCCUGUGUGCCCCACAGACCUAAUAUAUGUCCGGACAGCUUGGAUGCUGCCACGUAAGGUCACUGCUGUGGCGAGUCUUGCUAUGUCUGGGUGCCCCAUAGUCACAGAACACCUGGACACCGCCACAUGCAGUCAUCAUCAUGUUACUUUCAGGAGCCUCAACACGAGAGCUCAACACUGCCUCCGACCAGUCCCUCUGAGGCCCACAGGUCUGUCAUCCCAUAGGCCACCACACAGAGAAAUGCUGGCUGAGGGUCACUUGCUUGCUCUGUGCCCCAUGAGGCAGCACCUGCCCCAGAUGGACGGGGCUGUGAGGGGUGUCUCCAGGCACAAAGGCCCGAACACAGGAAGCCUGUGACCAUGGCAGCCUUGUCUUAUGGGCGCAUAUGUGCGUGUGUGGCUGAGUCUCUGACAGCUGUGAGUGUGUGUGAGCAGGGUAAGGGUACGUGAGGGGUCUGAGAGGAGUGGGUGCUUGUCCCCCAAACCUGCAUGAAGCAAGAACAACUCCUGGCCAGGCCCUGUCCUCCCCACGUACCCCUGCAUCCCCAGCCUCGACCCAGGGACAUGCAGGGCUCACAGGAGACAGGGCUCAGGCUGCCGGAGCUCCAACCAAACUCUGUCCCACUUCACGCACGGACUGUCCUGGGCAAAGGUGUUCACCUUUCCGAGCCUCGGUUUCCUUAUCUGUAAAGCAAAGCGACACCAGCAAGCCUGUGAGCAUUGUGUAUAUAGCAGACAUGGAGGUCCUGCAGCAGGAGGUGCUCAAUAAACACAAAGCGACUGAAGGAUGGGACCAGCAAGCCUGUGAGCAUUGUGUAUGUAGCAGACAUGGAGGUCCUGCAGCAGGAGGUGCUCAAUAAACACAAAGCGACUGAAGGAUGGGAUGUGCGAGAAUCCCAGUGGUGUGCACCCAGGCCGCGACACAUGGUGGUGUGCAUGACCAACUGCCCAACUCUCAUUGUCAUGGUGGGCCUGCCCGCCAGGGGCAAGACCUACAUCUCCAAGAAGCUGACUCGAUACCUGAACUGGAUUGGUGUGCCCACUCGGGAGUUCAAUGUUGGCCAGUAUCGCCGGGACGUGGUCAAGACCUACAAAUCUUUUGAAUUUUUUCUCCCCGACAAUGAAGAGGGCCUGAAAAUCAGGAAGCAGUGUGCCCUGGCAGCCCUCCGUGACGUCCGGCGGUUCCUUAGUGAGGAGGGGGGACAUGUGGCGGUUUUUGAUGCCACAAACACCACCCGAGAACGGAGAGCGACCAUCUUUAAUUUUGGAGAACAGAAUGGCUACAAGACCUUUUUUGUCGAGUCCAUCUGUGUGGAUCCUGAGGUCAUAGCUGCCAACAUCGUGCAAGUGAAACUGGGCAGCCCUGACUAUGUCAACCGCGACAGUGAUGAGGCUACGGAGGACUUCAUGAGGCGCAUUGAGUGCUAUGAGAACUCCUACGAGUCGCUAGAUGAGGACCUGGAUAGGGACCUGUCCUAUAUCAAGAUCAUGGAUGUGGGCCAGAGCUACGUGGUGAACCGUGUGGCUGACCACAUCCAGAGCCGCAUCGUAUAUUACCUCAUGAACAUCCACGUGACCCCCCGCUCCAUCUACCUCUGCCGGCACGGGGAGAGCGAGCUCAACCUCAAGGGCCGGAUUGGCGGGGACCCAGGACUGUCCCCUCGGGGCAGGGAGUUUGCCAAGAGUCUAGCCCAGUUCAUCAGUGACCAAAAUAUCAAGGAUCUGAAGGUCUGGACAAGCCAGAUGAAGAGGACAAUCCAGACGGCUGAGGCACUGGGUGUGCCCUAUGAACAGUGGAAGGUCCUCAACGAGAUCGAUGCGGGCGUCUGUGAGGAAAUGACCUACGAGGAAAUUCAGGAUAAUUAUCCACUGGAGUUCGCCCUGCGGGACCAGGACAAGUACCGGUACCGGUACCCUAAAGGGGAGUCCUACGAGGACCUGGUCCAGAGACUGGAGCCUGUCAUCAUGGAGCUGGAGAGGCAAGAGAAUGUGCUGGUCAUCUGCCACCAGGCUGUGAUGCGCUGCCUGCUGGCCUACUUCCUCGACAAGGCAGCAGAACAGCUGCCCUACCUCAAGUGUCCGCUGCACACAGUCCUGAAGCUGACUCCUGUGGCAUAUGGUUGUAAAGUGGAGUCCAUAUUCCUGAACGUGGCUGCUGUGAACACGCACCGGGACAGGCCUCAGAACGUGGACAUCUCAAGACCUCCAGAGGAAGCCCUUGUCACGGUGCCUGCUCACCAGUGACCAUGUUCAUCCACUGUGACCACUAGGCAGGCACUGCUCUCUGCAGAGGGGGUCAUUCCAGGCCCUCCAGUGUGUGUGAUAGUCACCAUGCCAUGCAGGGAUAUUCUUGAAGCCACACAUGGCUGGCGGAACCCAGAGCCCCCACCCCAGCCCACCUGGCUCUUUGUUGACAGUCGGCGACAAGGUUGUGCGUGGCUCCUGACCUGCUGCUAAGAGUCACUUGACCAGACUGCAUCUGCAUGGGCUGCGCGGAGGUUGCCCAGCCCCAGUUUCUUCCGGCGCAGCUCUUAGGUGUUCACUCUCGCCAGCUCAGUUGGCUUUGUGAAGUGUGAAACCCUACAAUGUGAAAGGAAAGUGCUUGCUGUGAUGUUCCUACUGUGGCCCAGCUGCCCAGCAUGGACCUGGUGACUCUCCACAGGGCCUCUACCAUCCUCUCUGUGGCCACUUCCUGAGCCAGAGGCCAGGUCUUCAUGGGGCCCUGAGCUUCUGCUGCCUCUGGUGAGAGGGAGAGCCCUUCCCAUCCUUACCCACCAGGAACUAGAGCCCCAACCACAGCAGAUGCUUCCUGGGCAGCCACUGGCCAGGCCGUUGUAUCCAUGUCACCCUUAGUUGUGGGCAUUCAUGAAAGCAAUGCGCUUGCUUCAGCACAUUGGGAUGCACAGAAACGUGAGGGCAGGGGGGCAGUUGUGGUCGCCCCUCCCCAGUUGUGCAUGUACCCGGCUACUUAGGUAUGCUUAGGGGAGCUGGUGGCCAGGGGUGCCCCUUCAGGCCUGCUCUCACAGUGAAACCACUUCAAGACAGGGCAGGAAGUUACCUUCCUGGUGCACACACCGAAGUGCUCGAGGGAGAGGCUGCCGCCCCCUCUCCCCUUCCCUGGCUGUGGACACUGGCAGCCAAUGGGGAGGCGGCCUCUCCCCUGUUGCUGCCCGUGUCCACACAGGAAUGUACACUGGUGGCAGAAACAUGCAUUUGCCAUAAAUAAUUCAGAAACACUUGUAUGGUCCUGUAAAACUUCUCUGGUGUUUGUUGACUUCUGCCUGUGGGUCUGAGGAAGGGAGAAGGCAGAACCCAUAGGCAGUCCCUGGGCAAGGGAGGAUUUUCCCGGCCGCAGCACAGCCUUCCAUUCAUGUGCACGUGAGUCUGGUGAAAAUGGCCUUGUGAAGUCCAGUGUCUGUCAUGCCCCUGAGUUCUUUUGGUCCCAGAGAGGCAGCCUGGGCAGUCUGUUUACAGCUGGCAAACAGACUGGCUGGCAAGUUGUGGGGCUGGGUCAGAAAGUGUCUGGACUUGUAAUCGGGUGCCCUGCUGUCCACAGGUGGACUCUGGGGAAGCCAGGCCCCUGGAUCCCAAGUCCUUUGUGUCCGGAGCCUUUCCUGGCCUGUGCCUGGAGGGUAGCACAUCUUUCCAGCCUCCCAGGGCUUUGCAGCCUGCAGAUGCCACCUGUCCCUGAGAGAAGUUAGCGUCCCUGGCCCUGGCCGGUGGUCUCUCAUCCUUGUGUGCUGCUCUGCUAAGAGAUGUCCAAGGCGGAGCCGGGGCAAGAUCCUUCCAGACUCAUCUGUCAGAGCCCCAAGCCCUUUAGACCCAGAGCCCAAGGACCAUGCCUUUGGGACAUUAGGACUGCAGCCUUUGCUUCUGUGUAUUUUGGAGUUUUGGUGACUUUUGUCACCUGGACACACUCAUUUGUUAGCCAUAGUGGGUUCCCUUGGUCAGCAACAGUGCAUGUACCUCUGGAUGUCAUCUGAGGUGAGACCACCGAGGCCUUUUCUCUCUGUGUACAGAGGGGAGUUAGGAGUUGCUGGACUGGAUGCAUUACGAGGACUGGGGACAGGGUAGAGGGACAUCCAGGGAUCAGGGCAUGAGUGGGGGCAACCCCCCGGCCUCUGCCCUGGCAUGGUCUCCGCAUGGGCUGAGGUGUAGCUGAUUGGCUGCCACAUUUCGGCCAUGCUGGCUGGCGUGCCCAUGUUGCAGAUAUUUUCCCGAGUUCCCCAGAAUGGAUGGUAUUGAAUCUCAGCCACAUGCAACACUGUGUCCAGCAUUCUUUGCAAUAAAUACUUUUUAAAAAAUAA